GCAAAACUUCCAUCCUGUCCACGUGAAGUUGUCGCUGCCUUAGAGAGGGGGAAAGAGCUGCGGGAAAAGCCGGGGAGUGACGACUGCGGCGGCUGGGCGCGCUCUCUCAUUUUCUUUUCUUCUCCUUUCCCCCCUGUCGCAGUCCGGAGUUUUGGCUCCUCUCCUUUCCUCCUCCCCCUCGGAGCCGGCUUCUCCCUCCGCCCCGCUUCUCCCCCGCUUGUGUACGCUAUUUGUUGUGGGGUGGCCGAAGGGGAUGUCCUGUUUUCACCAGAGGCACAGCGCGAAGGGGAAACUUCGACACUGGAAGGAACGAGAAUAAAUACUUAAUUACGGACGCACUGAACCGCGGCUGGGACAGACACUUCGGGAACCCGAGGCGGACCGGGCGACGAGAUAGUCAUUUUUACUUGAAGGAAGCUGCUUCUACUUGGGAGUGGCAGGAGAAGUGAGAAAACCACAUGGAAGACUCCCAGGAUUUAAAUGAACAAUCAGUAAAGAAAACGUGCACAGAAUCAGAUGUUUCACAAUCUCAGAAUUCCAGGUCUAUGGAAAUGCAGGACCUAGCAAGUCCUCAUACUCUUGUUGGAGGUGGUGAUACUCCAGGUAGCUCCAAACUGGAAAAAUCUAAUCUCAGCAGCACAUCAGUUACUACAAAUGGGACAGGAGGGGAAAACAUGACUGUUUUAAACACAGCAGACUGGUUGCUGAGUUGCAACACCCCCUCUUCUGCAACAAUGUCUCUUCUUGCAGUCAAAACAGAGCCCUUGAACAGCAGUGAAACCACAGCCACGACUGGAGAUGGAGCGCUUGACACUUUUACUGGGUCAGUAAUUACAAGUAGUGGCUACAGCCCCAGAUCAGCACAUCAGUAUUCCCCACAGCUGUAUCCUUCCAAGCCCUAUCCACACAUUCUUUCUACACCAGCAGCUCAAACAAUGUCUGCCUAUGCAGGCCAGACUCAGUAUUCGGGGAUGCAGCAGCCAGCCGUCUACACAGCCUACUCACAGACAGGACAGCCCUACAGCUUGCCCACUUACGAUUUGGGUGUGAUGUUGCCAGCCAUCAAGACAGAGAGUGGACUUUCCCAAACUCAGUCCCCAUUACAGAGUGGCUGCCUCAGUUACAGCCCAGGGUUCUCUACCCCACAGCCAGGCCAGACACCUUAUUCUUACCAAAUGCCAGGUUCUAGUUUUGCACCAUCAUCUACUAUUUAUGCAAAUAAUUCAGUUUCCAAUUCAACGAAUUUCAGUGGUUCACAACAGGAUUAUCCAUCCUAUACAGCCUUUGGCCAAAACCAGUAUGCACAGUAUUAUUCAGCAUCAACGUAUGGAGCGUAUAUGACAUCGAAUAACACAGCCGAUGGCACACCCUCUUCAACCUCUACUUAUCAGUUGCAGGAAUCUCUCCCAGGACUGACUAACCAACCAGGUACAGAUCUUCACCCAGGAGAGUUCGAUACCAUGCAGAGUCCCUCCACACCCAUCAAAGAUCUUGAUGAGAGAACCUGUAGGAGUUCUGGGUCAAAGUCCAGAGGAAGAGGCCGGAAAAAUAAUCCCUCCCCGCCUCCUGAUAGUGACCUGGAGCGUGUGUUUGUCUGGGAUUUGGAUGAAACCAUCAUUGUUUUUCACUCACUGCUCACCGGGUCUUAUGCACAGAAGUAUGGCAAGGAUCCCCCCAUGGCUGUAACCCUUGGACUCCGCAUGGAAGAAAUGAUUUUUAAUCUUGCUGAUACUCAUUUGUUUUUUAAUGAUUUAGAGGAGUGUGAUCAAGUUCAUAUAGAUGAUGUUUCCUCUGAUGAUAAUGGGCAGGACUUAAGUACCUACAGUUUUGCAACUGAUGGCUUCCAUGCAGCUGCAAGUAGUGCAAACCUUUGUUUGCCAACAGGUGUAAGAGGAGGGGUUGACUGGAUGAGGAAGUUGGCUUUUCGUUACAGAAGAGUAAAAGAAUUAUAUAACACCUACAAGAACAACGUUGGAGGACUCCUUGGCCCUGCCAAGAGGGAUGCCUGGCUACAGUUAAGGGCAGAGAUUGAAGGUCUGACAGAUUCCUGGCUAACAAAUGCACUUAAGUCUUUAUCAAUUAUUAGCACUAGGAGUAACUGCAUAAAUGUCUUGGUAACGACAACUCAACUGAUCCCAGCACUUGCGAAGGUUCUACUCUAUAGUUUAGGAGGUGCUUUCCCCAUUGAGAAUAUUUACAGUGCAACUAAAAUAGGCAAGGAAAGCUGUUUUGAGCGUAUAGUGUCCAGAUUUGGCACUAACAUAACUUAUGUUGUGAUUGGAGAUGGCCGAGAUGAGGAGCAUGCCGCUAACCAGGUAACUUCACUCUGAACUUUAUCUCAUUUAUCUUCCAGGAAAAGAAAGUUGCUUUGAACGAAUAAUGCAAAGGUUUGGCAGAAAAGUAGUGUAUGUUGUAAUUGGGGAUGGUGUAGAAGAAGAACAGGCAGCAAAAAAGGUAACCUGUCUCAAACAAUGUCGGUGUGAUACUUCUAAUGCAAGCCUUUUUGUUUGCAUUUCUGUAGUUUGGCCCAAUGGCAGCUUGACAAAUGAUUUAAAUUUAUAGAUGCAAAGCAAUAAGAGCAUGAGAGGGUCAAUACUUACAUUCAAAUAAACCAUUUGGAGUUUAGCAUUUUUUGCCUGAAAUUUGAUAGGAAAUGCAGGGAAAUUUAGUUAUAUUUAUUUAUGUGUUUGAAAGUAUAUACAUAUAGUAAAUAUAUAUAGUAACAUAUAUAUUUGUGUGGGCAUGUAUACACAUGCUUAUAUAGAUGCAUAUGUAUAUAUUAAUACACAUACAAUGUGCACAGAUAUAGAUGAGCCAGGGGAUCUGCAAGAAAGAUUGGGGGGGAGAAUAACCAUUGUUAAGCACAUGAAAUUUAGCAAGAUAGAGAUUAAUGAGCUCCAUACAAAAGUCAUGUGAGUAGUUCAUGAGACCUGCAUGCCAUAUGGUCCUCGUGAGUGCCUGGAAGUAGGCAUGCUCCAUGAUAAGGAAUGCUGAGGGCAGAUUUAAUAGCUGAAGAAAAACUGCUACAAGAGAUUUUAAUAAGUGCUACUGAAAUGGGAUGUAUUGCUCAGAUCCUUUUGCACCAACUUGUCUUAGCCGUAAUGUGCCUCACAUCUCCUAGAAGAGUUUCAUCUGUUUUGGUGAGCCAGUGGUACUUGAUUGAAGCCAAGCAGCUGGCUUUGAACACAUUCAGAAGAUCCCAUGGGCCCUAAGUAUUUUAAUAAGCCUUUUCAUCUGGCCCGUAUUUCUGAAGAAGAAACCAAGGCAAUUAAAAACCAUUAAAUGGUUGGUUCAACAUCAAAAGAAGAAUGAUAUCAGGAUUGGCCCCCACCACCAGACUGUCAACUCCACCCUAAGAUCUACUGCUGCCUUCACCGAAUGAUAGAAAAAUAUCAUCUACCCAAGAUAAAAGUGAUAGAAUUUACAAAACAAAGCCAGAUGAUGAAUUAGUAUUUUUAAAACAAUGACAUGCCAGCCUAUACUGUUUUACAUAGAAAGAAUGUCAUCUGUAUCACCCUAAGGAGAUUUUAAAUCAUCAUCUAAUAAAGCCUUUGCCAUUUGCAUGUGCUGGAAUGUUUACCUGUUUUCAAAAAACAGUCAACAUAGACAGUUUUAUAGAAAAGUUUAUGGCUAUAAGAGAAAGAGAAAGGAAAUGAUGUAUGUUUCUAGUCGAUUUAAAUCAAGCAAAAUGGAGAAAAGGAAAGCACUUCCACUUUAGAAGUUUUGGUGACGUAUUGGCAGCCAUACUUGCUUUUCGAUUACAUUUAAGAGAGUAGGCUCAGGCUCUGCCUGCCACAGAACACCUCAGCCUUCAUUAGCAGUGUCAAUGACCCAAGACAGCACACUAGCCCCAAGCACGUCCUGUAUGAGGUCAGGGCUGCAGCCUCAAGAAAUACGGCUUUCAUUGCUGACUACUACUUCAAAUGCUUCCAGUCACACUGAACUGAAAUAUCUUCUGGAGUUUGUCAAUGUCCUGAGUCCAUGUUGUGAUUUUUCUUAUUGGCACCAUAGUUAUACACAACAAAGAGCAGCCAAUGAUUAGUAAUACAGCCCCACUCCUGCUAAAUUUACAUGUCUUUUAGCCUAUGCAAAUUAAAUUCACGUAUAUUUAGGUAAGGACUAAUAUAAUUCAGUUUUCCAAACCAGUAACACAAUAUGCUUUUGACAAUUAAAACUUAGCCGAGUCUACCUGUUUUCCACAGCAUUAAUGUUUAGAUUCGGUUUACCAGUUGUUAUACCUAAAACUUCAGGAGGGAAACGCAUAACCCUGAAUGGAAAACAAUCUCAGAUAGAAUGCUAUUUCCAAAUGGUUGUUUAUGUAGGUACAGUUUUGGUGAUGGUGAAGGCUUAUUAUUCUAUUUUAAAACAGAGGUGAUUGGUUUCUCUAGUACCCAGAAUGCAUGCUUUUCUUUGGAUGUAGCGGUAAUCGCAUGUGCAGAAAUGUUAAGUACUGUUUUGUUGUUACAAAUAGAUCUGAGCUGAAUGAAAAAAUGUUACUUCUAUGUGAAUUUCAGUGACUUAAUUUGACCUAGACAUAUUUUGUCUGAGAAAUUUAAGAAGAAAUAUCAAAGUUUAGGAAUAGGAAUGUCUAGCUGCGCUCUUCCAUAGAAACAUGUAAUAUUAAUACAAGCUGUAUAUGUAGUUUGAAAUUUUCUAGAAGCUACAUUUUACAAAAUUAAAGAGAAACAGGUAGAAUUAAUUUUAAUAACAUGUCAACCCAGUAUACCCAAAAUAAUUGUCUUGAUAUCUAAUUAAUGUAAAAAUUAUUGAAGUCAUGUUUACAUUCUUUUUUGUUUGUUUGUUUUGUCCUAAGUCUUUGAAAUUCAUUGUGUAUUUUAAACUGGACCAACCACAUUUCAAGUGCUCAAUAGCCACAUGUGGCUGGUGGCUACCAUAGUGUGCAGCAAGGAAUUAUAUAGCAAUAAGGAUUAUUAUGCUACUUAGUUCUUAAAUAAAAUAUCUUUUGCAUGUUUUAUAUCUAUAUACUCAUUUCCCUUAUAUACAUGAAUAUUUUAUACGUACAUAUUCUAGAAGAUGUCAUCAGCCCAAACUUAACAAAUCAUGCUUUUGUUUUGUCAGUUCCUGUAAUGCAGUGUUUUUUCUUUUUCAUUAUCAUCGCCAGUGGGGACUCUUUAGACAGUUUUUUUCUAAUUACUCCCUUUCAUGAAAUUUUAAUGUCACAUAUGUACUGUAUACUAUUAUAGUAUAUCUUUUGAAGGCCACAAACCACUGUAAUGUCUAAGAUUUUCUGCCCCACAAGAGCUCAUUUGUGUCCCUUUGGAGAUAUCUUCCCCAUUGAAAAUGUAUGCUAGAGUACUUUCUCUCAAUUCUACGCCAGUGAAAUAAAUCAGGUCGACUCUACUGGCUUAAGUUAUUGGUUGUCCCAGACAAGUAAGAAAGUUAUAAUCCCCACCUUUUUUUUCUACUUUAUGUAGUCCUGCUUCAAAUUAUUUUUAUACAGAAAGGAAUUCACCCUCUUUUCUUCCUAGAUUAACAAAAUUAAGAAGUUUGUCAUUUUGUUUCAUUUUAUUUUUAAUUGAGAGGCCCGUAGGAGUGAUGCACUGAUUAAAACUUGCUUUCCAUUAGCCAGGUAGGAUUUUGAUGCCCACUUGCUUUCCCAGAUGUUGAUGUUGGUAGCGAUACUUCCAGAAUAAAUAUUAAACUAUCUAAGAAAUGUUAAUAUUUGCUAUUAUUCUCAUUAAAAUCCAGUUCAGAUCUAUUUCUCUGUUACUUUGACAGUGCCAUAUUGGUGCUGCCAAGCCUUCACAUAUGAUCAUCCCGCCUUUAAACUCUCUCCCCUGAACUUGGGUGGACCACACAUCCCUGUGUGUGCUGCUGCUUCAUUGAGACAAUGGUUGUGAUCUCUCUCCAUGCCUCAUUCCUUCCCCUUCUCUCUCCCAUCCCUCCUUCUCCUAACCACACAGCACAACAUGCCCUUCUGGAGGAUAUCCAGUCACUCAGACCUCCUGGCUCUCCACCAAGCACUGGAAUUAGAGUAUUUGUAACUGUGUUCUUUAGCCGGAGAUCCAUUUUUUAUAUUUCAAGUACACUGAAUUUUUAUGUGUGAUUCAAUGCCUCUGGCUCUACACAUAUAAAUUGUCUUAAUGGAUGAAAUCAUAUUUGGAAUAAAAAUUCCAGAAUGAAGAAUUCAGAUUGCUGAAUGGAGUUAAACUUUAGUGCUACAGAAAAGAAACUCUAUGGUCUUAUAUUUACAACACUUUAAUGGGUUUUUUAAAAAUCUGUGGAGGUUGCUGGUACACACCAAAUGAGUCCAAACUGGAAUGAGCAGCUUUAGCAAAGAACUCUUACCCUGGCAAAGCAGCAACACACAUGCUCCGUCUGACAAGGUGGUCAACAACAUUCCUCAAAAUGGGAGAUCUUCUCAGCCCUGAGGUUUGAAUCUGACUUUAGCCUACCUAACCCAGAAAAUCUGAAUUGGAAUGCACUCAGACUGUAUAAGGACAGUCCUAUUUAGACAUGUAAUUUGUGUAAAUUAUUGAUGAAAAUAAUUUACUGUGACUUUAUUAGCAGCUGACUUUCAAAGUGGAUGCAAUUUUUCUUUCUUUUGUUGGGGAGGGGAAUGGGAGGGGAAAUGGGAAUAUAAUAUUGUCUCUUUUUUAAGUUUGGCAAACAGAAUGUUCAUACUGAUGUGUUGUGCCUUAAAGACAAGACAGCAUUUGUGUGUUACAAUGUAACUUUGGUUAAAAUCUCUGUAGAUAAUGAAAAAAAACAAAAAAAAAAACCUUUGUGAUGAUUCUUAACAUGACCAAAUUUAAAAGUCAAGCUCUCAGAGCUUAAUUACCGCAUCAGCAAGAAACUGAGUAUUUUUUGCAAUAAGAAAACAACAAUAAUAAAGGAAAGCUUGUGUUUCAUUUGGGUUCUUAAUAAUUCCAAUAAUUGUAUGAGGCAACUAUUUGCGCAUCCAACCAUGAGUGGAAGGUUUGGGAAAGACUGUGGGACCUUUACUUAGAAAGUGAAAUGUAUGUAGAAGUCUCAAGUACCCCUUCUACAGUUUUACUGGAGAAAACUAAGAGCCAUAUUCAUGACAACUUGCACAGUUUUGAGGUUGAGACUUUUGAUAUGUGUAAGUUGCAUAGAGGAGGAUAUUAUCAUGCAAAUCAUGAGCAAUUAUCACAUAAACUUUUUUAGAAUGUGCCAUGAACAUGGCAUAAAAUUCACAUUGAGUGCACAGGGCUUAAAAUAAAGCUAAGUAUGUUUAUUCCCAAUGCCAUGGCAAAAAUGAUAAUAUCAUCAGAAAUGGAAGGCAGUUCUCCCAGAUGGUGUCUAAUGAAAGCAAUGAGUCUAUGAAAAUUUUACCUAGAAUAUCAUCAUAAAUUAAAUUAGCAAGUGCGCUGGAUCUUGGCAGCGCUGCUGAAAUGACAACAGUAAAAUAAUACCUGGUUCUCCAUCUGAAUACAUCAAUGCAGGUUCUCCUCGUAACAGACUUGCAUAUGUUUGUUAGUUUCUGCCUGUAUUGUCACUGCGCAACGGAUGGCAUUCAUUACAAGAAGAGCCCAUCAUCGUUGUGUUUGCAUGGUUUUUUUCCUUGUGUGUAGCCCAUGUUGGGAACACGAUACAGGUUCUCCUCUUAUUUCCUAUGACACGAUUUCCCUUGUGGAAAUUUAAGACUUUAAGAACUAGAGUAUUUUUAUGGUGUCUGCACCUGCAGUUCUGUGUUUAAAAUGUCAUAAUGUGGAUCCUGGAGUCAGGCUACUAGUCAGUGCCCCUAGCCAGAGGCUGGUUCAUGAGUUCAUCAACUGAGGCCUCUGUGGCUUCAAUAAAGUCUACAUUUUGCUCACAGAUCACAACAUUCACUGUGGAAAUAUGAUUUCAUUUCUUUAGGCUACAAACCUGUAUUUCUUUACUGAAUGCUAAGGCCAUGUUUAUAUUGGGUAGAAAGAUAUUGAGAUCCCAAUUUUGUACAAGAUUGUGAUUUCAUUAUCUAAACCUUAAACUUAAUCCUUUAAAUUUUGUAGCUUUUGGCUGCAUCUGCCCCAAGUACUAUUCCAGGCAAAUUAAAGUUGGAAUACCUUUAAUAAUAUAAAAAUAAUGAUAGUAAAUCUUAUACUUCUGUUGGCCCUUAGCUUGAAAAUAGCAGUUAAAAAAAUUUAAAUGUUGCCUUGAUUAUCAGUACUUAAUUAUGUUGUGCACUAAAACCUUAAAUAUUUAUUACUGUGAAUAAAAACAAAUUAUCUUUACUGUAUAGCUGGUUUCUUUAAAUGUUGAUAGAAUUGUGGCAUUACAUCUAAAUUUGUAAGUCUUUUCAUAUCAAACAAGCAAGGCUUUUUAUGCUGCUAAGUCUGUGGGUGCAGAAAGAAACACCCCUUGGAAGGGCAAAGAGAAGCCGGCUGGUUGCAUCACCCCGUGCAGUUUCUCACACACAUCUCUUUUUCUGAUUCUGUGUUCAGAAGAGGCUGCCGGCAUAAAACCUAAAUGCAAGGUUGACGGAGAACAGCUUGUCUGGCACAACAAUGGUGCAGGCCCACGAGCCAGCAUCACAGCUUGGCCAUGGGACGUUGAGUAUGCACAAACUAGAACUCUUCCCUUCCCACCUUAGGAAUAGAAAAUCCUCUUCCUUUCUAAUCUGAAAAACGAAAACUGAACAAACACAAAACCAACCCCUUGGCAGUUCCCACCUCCUAUUGACAUAUGGAAUAUUGUGCCUUAUUGUAAACCAGUUUGAAAAAUGUUCUGUAACUAAAGUGGGUUUUCGGCUAUUAUGUAUACAGCUUGGUAUAUUACUACGAAAGAUAACCACCUUGUGUUGCACCUUAAAAAUAUCAAGACCAUGUAAUUUCCAUAACAAAAUAGGUGGCCUGGCUAUGGUAUUAUAGCAUACAAUUAGGACACUAUGCCCCUGCAAAAUUUUGUAAAUCAAAUUCAGAGGCAAAAACAUAUUUUAGAAUCAUACAGUUUGCACACGACAAGUAGGUAAUAACUGUCUCUAAAAAUGUUUUCUCCUUAGUCCGCAAUGAGCUAAGAUUCAGAAUAGUGUCAACAGCAUGCUCCUAUAUGAAGUUGUUUUUUUUAAAGCACAUUUGUUUAUGACAAGCCUACAUUCUCAGUGAAUAUGGCAUUUAGUAUUUCUUUUGAAAACAAACUUAAGCAUCAUGAGCCAAAGUUGCACUUUGACUCCCAACUACGGUAGCAUUAUGGACAUCUCACAAUGUCAAGGGUUUCUGUUAUGUAUUAGUAAAGUAUAGAUUAUUGGGGCCUACAUAAUUUAAAAGAAAUGUAAAUUAAUAUUAAAAGCUUGUAAAAAUAUGUAUAUCUUUACUAUUUCUCAAUAAAUACCUUUGCAAUUGUUUUCAUUUCCUUCACCCUCCCA